ACUCCUGAGUUCAAGCAGUCUGCCCGUGUCAGCCUCCCAAAGUGCUGGGAUUAUGGGCAUGAGCCACCAUGCGGGCCUGAUGUAAGAAUUCUUAAUAAAUAAGUAAGGAUGGACCUGAAUACUUACUAAAAGCUCUGAGGCCAUGGGUGGAGUUGGCUUAAUCUAGGGUGAUCUGAUUGGGCUGUUUUGGGAAUUAGUUGGAUUCCCCUGAGAAAUAUCUUCUGUUUUCUCUCUGGAGGGGGCAGGCUUGGAUAUCAACAUCCUGGAAGUCAAGGGGGUUGAGAACUAGGGGUUCCUGUAUUUGGUAUAUUGUUCUGUAUUCCUCCUGUUUCAGUGUGAUACCUGUGUCCUCAGAUUUGCCUGCUCCUCUUUGUCGAAGAGGCUCUCUGUUCAUUUUCUUUAGAAAAUAAACAUAAUCUCCGCUGGGUUGGAGAGGGGCAACCAUGAUGAGUGGUGGUGGGAUCUGAGGAUCUGACUGUACCUUACUAACCAACUCUUCUGUCUUUAGACUCAUUUUUACCCCAUUCUUUCAAAGACAUCUGGUGCCACAAAUUCCUGAGUUUUGAAGGGUUCUGUGGGGGAAGUCACAUUGCUUUUCUACUUUAUCCAGAGCCAACUUAGGAGUCUGUGUGAUCAGUUACCAUGUGUGUAAGUGCUUUCCAGCCUUGAAAUGUCAUUUCUGUAGUUCUCUCCUGUUCUCUUUGUUCUUACAGGUUUAUGCAUUAAACUACUUUAUUGCAGUUUUAGUGGGACUACAAGAGGGAGCAAAAAGGAAAUGUUUGUGUAUAAUCCUUGACCUUUACCUGGAAGCUCUCCUUCCAGUGUUUUCCAGGAAUGAUGGGGCCUGGAAAAAGGCAUGUAUUUCAGAGCUGUGGGAGGAUGGUGCCAGGGCCUUGUUUACAAAGUCCAAGUUGGAAGUGACUUGAGGUCACCUGGCUUGGUUCCUUGUUUCUAGGCGGGACUUCUGAAGGCAGAUGGAGCUCCUCCUGUCACCUUGGAAGGUGCUCCUGUAUUUACAUUUCUGGCAUUUGUAGUGAACAAAACAGUGGAAAAUCCUCAUGCAAAAUACAUAGAAAUGCUGGAAAAAGUAUAAUAAACACCCUUUUAAAAUGCAUAUACAUUGCUGCAUGUAUAAGAAGUAAGGGAAAAACAAGAAGGAGCUGGAAACUAGAGCUGUAUGCCUUCACUGACUGAAACUGCUGAUUCCUUGGGGACUUUGCCUGUCUUUAUAAUUUAGAGAUGUGGGUUUAAGUAGCAGUGUGGACAAUAGGAGAGAAGAUGUGGAAUUGAGACUGAGGCCUUUGCAUGGCUUCAGACUUCUGUUGUGUUAUACCUUCAGUAAAAAUGUGGGCCAGAAGAAACAUGUCUUUGUUGACAAAGAGACUAAAUAAUGAAAUUGUCUGAGACUGGGUAGGGUUGGGGUUGGGGUAGUUUCCCCGAGAAUUUAUAACCAUAGGCCUAUGCUCAUGUGAGCUUGGCAUUUAUACCAUCCUGUUCUCUGGUAAACUAAGUUGAGAAAUUAAAGUGGUUCCAAAUAGUUAAUGUCCUAGGGAGAUUGGCAGAAGGCAGAAAUAUAAGUUACCUUUGAAAGGUUGCCCCUUCAAACUUGGCCUCAAAGUAGUCCAACAGAAAAGGCCCCACUGAACAUAAGCUCAGUAUUCAAAAUUCUAAAACCACAUGAGGAAACAGUACCAUGAAUAAAGUCAGAAAUAACAAAUGUCAGAAGCAGACUUUCAAGAAGUUAAAUUACAGAAUUCUAAGAGAGAUUUGGAAGUAGGCCAAAGUACAGAAGUAUCAAAAUUGACCAGGAAGUUUUUUUUUAAUAGAACUUCUAGAAAUGAAAAAAUAGAAUAAUUGAAUUUAUAAAUUGAGUAGAAGAACUAAACAACAGAUUAGACAUAGCUAAAGAGAGAAUUCGUGAAUUGGAAGUUGAUCUUCAGGAAUUACCUGUAAUGGUGUUUAGACACAGAAUUGGAAAUUAGGAAAGGAGGGUUAAGAGACUGGGCAGAAUAAGAAGGUCUAAUAUGCUUAUAAUAGGAAUUUCAGAAUCAUAGAAUUUGGAGAUGCAAUAUUCAAGUUGAUAAUAGCCAAGAAUUUGUCAGAAUUGACAAAAAACACAAAUCAUUAGACUAAAGGCAUAGUGAACCCCAAAUAGUAUAAAUUUAAAUAUAUACUUAGACACAUACCUUGUAGUGAAACUGCCAAGAGAGAAAGCAGCCAGAAAGAAAAAAACAGAAUAUCUGCAAAGUUAAAUUAAUAGCAGACUUUUCAGCAACAGUAGUGGAAGCUAGAAAAUAGUGGAAUAAUAUUUUCAGAGAGCUGAGGUAAAAUAACAAUCUAAAAUUUUAUGUUCAUCUAAAUUGCCAUUCAGGAAGAAAGACAAAACAUUUUGAGAAAAGCAACAAAGGCUCCUCUGCCAAGAGAUCUCUACUGAAAUAUUUUUUUUCAGUAAGGACAGUGAUCUCAGAAAGAAAGGCAGAGAUGCAGGGAGAGAUGACUGUAUGGAUGCUUACAAAAUAUAGACACAAAUAAUGUCUGAUUUGGGAGCUGGGUAGUAAGAACAGUGACACUAAAUACGGAACACAAGCAAUAUGUUAAAUUAGAUGUACAUUGGAAGAGUCAUUAGAGUUUAAAAUAUUUAAGUUCCAAUGAGGGAUGGUAGAGAUGUUGAUUUAGGCUUUUAGUAUAAGUGUACCCAUUAAAGUUUAUAGGCCUAGCUUACAACGGAAUAGGAAUGAGAUGUAUAACUUUAAAAGUGGCUAAAAUAGGAAAUUUUAAAAGAUAAUCCAAAUAGAGGUAACGGUAGAAAAGAAACAAAUUUAAACAUACCCAGUAAUCAUAUAUAUAAACAUACCCAGAAAUCAUAAAUGUAAUGAGACCGAACUCUAAUUAAAAGAUGGUGUUAGAUUGAAUUGGGGGGAGGGAAGAGAGAAAGAUUUUUUGUUUAAGUUAGAAAAGGUAAUUUUCUCUAAUACUAACACACGAAAUGUCAUAUAGCUAUGUUAACAUCAGAUAAAAUGGACUUUUUGGCAAAGAGCAUUCAUUACAAAUGAAGAGGGUUACUAUAUAGUAAGAAAAAUUUUAUUACCAAGAAUAUAUAAAAUAAUUUCUGUAACUCAAAGGAAAAGUAAUCCAGUAGAAAAAUGAGAAAAGAUACAAACAAACAGUUCUCAGAAGGAAAUGUUAGUAAUCACAAGAAGAUGAUCAGUCUCACAAGUAAUCAGGGAAAUGCAGAUCCAAAUUGUGUACCAUUUCACACUCACCAGGUGAACCCCAGGUGGGGGCUGUCAUCUGUUGGGAACUUGGAUUGGCACAUCCACUUUGGAGAACAGUUUAACAGUAUUUAGUCAGUUGAUCUUUAGACUCUAUGACCUAGCCAAGAAACGCCCACACAUGAGUGCACACACACACGCACACACACAAAUGUAAAAAAGAAGUCAUGAUGGCAUUGCUGAGAUCAACAAACAUAAAUAACCUGAGUCCAGUAGGCUCUGGGCGUGGGGAGGCUGAGACACGGGAGUGCAUCUACUACAACGCCAACUGGGAGCUGGAGCGCACCAACCAGAGCGGCCUGGAGCGCUGCGAAGGCGAGCAGGACAAGCGGCUGCACUGCUACGCCUCCUGGCGCAACAGCUCUGGCACCAUCGAGCUCGUGAAGAAGGGCUGCUGGCUAGAUGACUUCAACUGCUACGAUAGGCAGGAGUGUGUGGCCACUGAGGAGAACCCCCAGGUGUACUUCUGCUGCUGUGAAGGCAACUUCUGCAACGAACGCUUCACUCAUUUGCCAGAGGCUGGGGGCCCGGAAGUCACGUACGAGCCACCCCCGACAGCCCCCACCCUGCUCACGGUGCUGGCCUACUCACUGCUGCCCAUCGGGGGCCUUUCCCUCAUCGUCCUGCUGGCCUUUUGGAUGUACCGGCAUCGCAAGCCCCCCUACGGUCAUGUGGACAUCCAUGAGGACCCUGGGCCUCCACCACCAUCCCCUCUGGUGGGCCUGAAGCCACUGCAGCUGCUGGAGAUCAAGGCUCGGGGGCGCUUUGGCUGUGUCUGGAAGGCCCAGCUCAUGAAUGACUUUGUAGCUGUCAAGAUCUUCCCACUCCAGGACAAGCAGUCGUGGCAGAGUGAACGGGAGAUCUUCAGCACACCUGGCAUGAAGCACGAGAACCUGCUACAGUUCAUUGCUGCCGAGAAGCGAGGCUCCAACCUCGAAGUAGAGCUGUGGCUCAUCACGGCCUUCCAUGACAAGGGCUCCCUCACGGAUUACCUCAAGGGGAACAUCAUCACAUGGAACGAACUGUGUCAUGUAGCAGAGACGAUGUCACGAGGCCUCUCAUACCUGCAUGAGGAUGUGCCCUGGUGCCGUGGCGAGGGCCACAAGCCGUCUAUUGCCCACAGGGACUUUAAAAGUAAGAAUGUAUUGCUGAAGAGCGACCUCACAGCCGUGCUGGCUGACUUUGGCUUGGCUGUUCGAUUUGAGCCAGGGAAACCUCCAGGGGACACCCACGGACAGGUAGGCACGAGACGGUACAUGGCUCCUGAGGUGCUCGAGGGAGCCAUCAACUUCCAGAGAGAUGCCUUCCUGCGCAUUGACAUGUAUGCCAUGGGGUUGGUGCUGUGGGAGCUUGUGUCUCGCUGCAAGGCUGCAGACGGACCCGUGGAUGAGUACAUGCUGCCCUUUGAGGAAGAGAUUGGCCAGCACCCUUCGUUGGAGGAGCUGCAGGAGGUGGUGGUGCACAAGAAGAUGAGGCCCACCAUUAAAGAUCACUGGUUGAAACACCCGGGCCUGGCCCAGCUUUGUGUGACCAUCGAGGAGUGCUGGGACCAUGAUGCAGAGGCUCGCUUGUCCGCGGGCUGUGUGGAGGAGCGGGUGUCCCUGAUUCGGAGGUCGGUCAACGGCACUACCUCGGACUGUCUCGUUUCCCUGGUGACCUCUGUCACCAAUGUGGACCUGCCCCCUAAAGAGUCAAGCAUCUAAGCCCAGGACAUGAGUGUCUGUCCAGACUCAGUGGAUCUGAAGAAAAAAGGAAAAAAAGUUGUGUUUUGUUUUGGAAAUCCCAUAAAACCAACAAACACAUAAAAUGCAGCUGCUAUUUUACCUUGACUUUUUAUUAUUAUUAUUAUAAUUAUUAUAAUUAUUAUUAUUAAUAUUAUUUUUUGGAUUGGAUCAGUUUUUACCAGCAUAUUGCUCUACUGUAUCACAAACAGCGGACACGUCAGCAGGCGUUGAGGUGCUGAGCUGUGGAUGCAGAACCAGCGCCAUGCUGAAGAGCCUCAGCCACCUCCUGUCCUUUGGGAUUCGUUUUUCCCGCUUUCUCUUUGUUUGUCGUCUCAGAAUCUGUGACACAAAGAAACCCAUCUCCUGUCUUAGGAAACCUAAUGCUGCAAACUCUACCUAGAGGAACCUUUGAAGACUGUUACAUAAGAACAUACCUUCCUCAGAAGAGGAGUUUCCUCUGCCCUCUGCCCUUCUCCCCUGCCUCCCUCCCUCCCCUCCUUUUAUUUUGUUUUAGUGAGCUUAAGAAACAGCAGAUGUGUCUUUCACGGAUCUAACGGGUGUUGUCCUGAUCGAGAAAAAAACUGGGAUGAGAAUGGUUUGGACUGGAGUUGGAAGGGGAGGACGGUACUGGGGGUAGGGUUUGGAACAGAGCUACACUGGACUCGGGCACAUUCGGAGCAGCAUCCUUUAGUAUGGAGGCUACUUCUCAGGUAACCAGGAAUUGAGGGGAAGGACCUUGUGGAGGCCGAGCAUUAACAGCAAGAGCGGGGUUUGGAGAAAGUCUGAGAUUGGGUGCAGCCCUGACUUACCUGCUGGCCCUGACCAGUUUCUUUUCACUAACUUGGCCUUGGGCAUAGGAUGAAACAUUUUUUCUGCCCUAAUUUUAAAACUAGGUGAGGGUAGAAUCAUCACAGGUUAGGAAUACAUUCUUCAUAAGACACGAUGCUGUAAAUACCCUUAAUGGACGAAAAGUUGAAAUACUUUUGUUUCCUCUUGGAGCAGUUCAGGGAAAUGCCCACAGGGGAUUGUCCUGCACAGAUAGGGCAAGAGGAUUUCCUGGGUGGAGUCUGCCAAGGCCUGCCUCGCUGGGGACCCCAGAGUCCUGCACCUCUGGUUCCGCCCCAGGUGGUGACAUUACUGUCCCCGUUCUGUGGCUCGUGGACAAGACUUUCUCCAGACCCCUUAAAGUGGUACAUAUUCUAAAAAACUGUUUUUCUAUUAUGCCAUAACCUUGCUCUAGUCAGUGAAUGUUCCUAAUGCUGCUGUUUCAACAUUUGAAUUCUUUUUAAUUUAUGAAACAUGCUAAAUUUUUUUUUUCAAACAAAACACACACAUCCACAUAUACACAUGCUUCGCUAUGUGGCUUCCAAGGUUUAAAUUUUGAAAAGUAAAAGAAUUAAAACUUCACGACCACAGAUCACCUCAAACCAGAAAUACCUCAGAAUUUUCUACUUAUGUAAGGUUUAUUAUAUAUUUUGUUAGUUGUGUUGUCUUGUAGUAAGUAUAUUUUAAUGUAAGUUGGCUUUUGUGACAAGGAAGUUUAAAAGAAAUAGAGAAAAAGAAAAAAGUUUGCAUCUUCUAGGGAGUGCUACCAUUUUUGUUUGAUAACGCCCCCUUGUAAAUAAUUGUCAUCAACUGUAGGUUGGCUGUCUGGGCCAAGUCUGGGCAUUUAUCAGUCUUGUUUGUGAAGGCUUUUCCUUCUGGUUUCUUUAGAUCAUUUUAUUUAAAAACAGUGCAUCUCUUCAUCGUGAGGGUAGGCAAGGCGGGGGCCGUGGGGAGAGGUUGACCUGGGUGAGAACUGAAGAGGCCGCCUCCUCUUGGGUUGUUUGGAGCUUCACAUGUAAUUCACAUGUAACAUGUAACUUGAUCGGUCAGUGUUCAGAAUGACAAGUAACCCCGCUUAAACUUGGUAGAAGGAUGGCCCUUAGACCUGAAUGGGGUGAUUUUACUUGGGAUUUAACUUCUUCAGCAAAUUAACAGCAACGUUGGAAGAGAUCUGUGGCGCCUCUGUGAAGCACACCGUGACUCAGGCCAGUCUUUUAGUGCAGCGUGUCUGGGAGUGAAGGGUUUUGCCCUUGCUGGUCUUGGAGUCCACAGUGUGAGGGGCACUGCACAUGCCUGGGCAUCUACCUAGUGUGCUAUGUUCAGUGUCUGGGGCUUACUGCCCCGGGGUCCUUUCCUCUGGGUGUUGGGGCACAGGGUGCUAUGGGAGGCCCAUUUGCUUCCCUCUCGGAGCUCAGUUUUUGCUUCAUGGGUCAAAAUGUGGGCUGGCCAAGUGGUUACAGGAACAGGGUUUCGGUAAGCUAUGUUGUCUUUUUUUUUUUUUUUUUUUUUUUUUUUAAUGGUUUGAUUUUGUGCUGUGGUAUUUUUUUUCCCUUAGAAUAAUUUUUAAUGGCAAAACAGGCCUUACAGCAGUUGCUUUUCUUUACCAUUUAUUUCUUUAAGAAGCUUUAAAAUAUUUAUUGAAAAGUGCCAUAUCUAAUUUCUUUAGCUUUCGCCUCAGGCAGUGCAGGCAUCUUUACUUUUCAUCCUCAGAAGAAACAAACGACUAACAAAUGUAGCAAAUUUACUGCAGGAAUAGUUAGGUCAUGAUACUACCUGAACACUAAACCCCAGCCUCUUUGUUUGGUUUUAGUUCCUCUGGGUGGUUUUUCUUUUGUGUGCUGGCUUGAUUCUUGUGAGAAGUUUUGACCUGGCCAAGGGAGGGUUGAGCCAUGGUUCUGGUGUGGGACUUUGCGGUCAAGACACAGUACAGACAGGUCAGGCCUGCGUGCCUUUUCUCUGGGUGGCCUCCCCGUUAGGCCCACCGUACGCUCAGCCACUAUAGUGUCCCUGUGGGGCCUUGCCAUCAGAUUGUGUGUCAGGAGAUGGUACCUUUUUGGUGUGGCUGGGGAGGAGUGUGGUCCAUGCCAGUUCUUUGGGCUUCAGGCCACUCUUCCCCUCAUGCUGUGGUGUAAAGUGCACCCAUCAGGUGGUAUAUCUGGUUCUGAUGGCAAGAAGAAGGUGGGGGAUCUCCUUAUAGGGCAUGGGUCUAGGAGCACAGAUGGGCCUUUUGCCCCGGGUAAAUGCUUGUCUGUUUGCUGUCAUGUGUUCUUUGAGGAGUGAGCCAUCUCGAGCCCUGCUUUGAAUUUACUGGGUCAUAGAGCCUCUGCCUGUGCUCUUUUCCAUAAUGACUUCAUGUGACAUGCACUUUUGGUGGGCUCAGAUAAUUGGUUUCUUUUUGUUUUUGACCUCAGGCUCUGUGGCAGACUGGGGAAAAUGGGGCCUGGCAUCAUUUUCCCUGUCAAUGGGAGGGGCUGUUCCAUGCAGGGUGGGAGGGGACCAAGUUAGCAGAGAGUAGCCAAGGAUCCUUGCUUCUUCCUUUCUAGUGUGCUGUCAUCCAAGCAGGCUCCUGGCUGUAGGGAUGGGCCUUGGGGAAGAAUCUUCUUUGAAAGCAUCUAUGAUAACUGAGAAGUCAUCCCUAGUUGGAGAAAUCCAGUAAUGAGCAGAAGGAGGAAGCAAGUGAGGACAGAGGCCAUUGUAUUACAGUGUCACGCAGAGGGCCCUCAAUGAUGGGGCAUUGGGGAAGGCUGUAGACAUAGUCAUCAGAACAUCCUGGCCUGGCAUAAGCUGGGUUUUCUCCUGGGACCAUUGGUCCUCAGCAGGAGUUCUUUGCAUGAGUUGCUCAGGGGCAAGGGCUGCAAGUGGGCUGUGCUUAGGAGAAAGUGACACCUGGCAGUGAGGGAAGAUGGUGAGCAUUAUUAGCCUUUGUUGUCCAGCAUGGCCUUCUUGUCCUGUCUGCUCUGGAGAGGAGCCUGUGGGACCAGUCCUGCCUGGGGAGGGCAUACCCACACGUGCCAGCUGAUUCUGACUCUGAAUACAUCAUGUCCGGACUUGGGGGUGUUUCUGCAGAAAAAGGAGGUUGUUUUUCAGCCUUGAACAUCUUCAGGAGGAUAGAGACUCUUGCUCACAUAUUCUUAGCAAAGGGAAGGGUCUCUCAUCUCCAGGCCACAGAGAUAGUUCUUCCAUUGCCCUAAGAGGCUAGGCUAACCCUCUUGACAUAACUUAGACAGCAAAGCACUUCAUCCUGUAGUUGGGCUCUGUCACCUUUCUCUUCAGUUGGCCACAUUCUCGUUUCCUCCAUCCUGCUAUGCUUUGUGUGCUCGGGCUGUGUGUGGGGUUUUUCCCUGGUGGAAGGAAGCCCAGCUGUGUAUUGAAUGUCCUUCAUGUGUUGUGUGUGGCUCAGAAAGCCUGUCACUUGGCCCCUGUGCUCUGAGCCGUGAGGGUGGGGAGGUGGCUGUUCCAUUAAAGUGGGAGUAUUGGAUGGCCCUCUUGAAACUAGAAUUUUGCCUUUUUUAGUAUGCAGUAUAAAGUUUCCAGCAUCUAUUGGUAACACAAAGAUUUGCUGGUUUUUAAAAUAAUACAGUAAGCAUAAGUAUGUAAGUUUUUAGAAUUGGUACUAGAAGUUGGACAGCUAGUUAUUCUCGAGAACUUUAUUUCACUAGAAAAAUAUACUAAUUGGAAAGCAGUUUCCAGGAGUUAACUCAGUUUAAUUUUCAGUCUCAGUUAUUUUAGCCUGUUGAGUUUUUGAUGGCACACCUUUGGAGAGAUGGCCACGCCUGAUUCCCAUUUCAGGGGCAUCAGACCAUACCUUUUUAAGAAGCUCCGUGAAUCUAGUCAUCUACCCUUCAUCCUGGGCGAACAGCCAAAAAGAGAAGGGGACAAGGUGUCUUUUUCUCCUUCUCACUGGGGUGACAUGAAUUCUUUUAGUUAAUGGCUGUUUGCAAAUUCUAAACUAAUGAAAUACUUAGCAGCUAACAUGUUCAAUCUAGUAAUGAUGAGUUUAAAUCUCAAUUGACAGUAAUGUUUUAGAUAAACAGGCCCAGUAAUUCAGUUGAUGAACUGUAUAUCUUCUCAGUCUAGAUUUGUAAAUGUUUAAUGAAUUCAGGGUUAUAAGCAUAGUUCUUUAAGUAAGAUUCCAGAUAGUUGAUUUGCAACCAGCAGUCUACCUAUGAAUGUAUCCCAAACCUUUAGAAGAUUGGAAAAGAUUUUUGAAAUAAUGAUUUAGUUUUGUAGGAAAAACACCCCCUUGAAAAUUAAUUCGGUUGACCCAGUAACAUUUUUUAAAACAAUUGGUGGCUCCAAAAGGCCUGCCAACAAAGAAAAGUCCAAAUUAUCUAGUGGGACAUUUUGAAUGUUUUAUGUUUAUUUUGGGUCCACUGUAAACUUUGGUUCAAAAAAGAAUUUGAAUUUAAAGAAUUUACCAUUAUUUAAAUUAUUACCAAGUUUUUACAUUUUCAUGAUGGUAUUUUCCAGGUAUGAAUGAAACAUGACUUUUUGAUUGUGGUACUUCCUGUAUCCCCUGUAGUGCCAAAACCAGUGAUACUUUAUUUGCUCCUAUGGCAGCUCAUAGAGGUAACCGAAGUGAUUUUUCCUCAGUAAUUGAAACACAUAUUCUCUAAAUGCCAAUGUGUGGUGAUGGGCCCUGCACUGCCUUCAUUUCUCUAGGGCAGUGUCUUUGGAUUGUCUAGGGCCUAGGUAAUUCUGAGAACUACUGUAAACCAACCACAGGGCACUAAAGCAAUGUACACACCACUCUUUGUGUGUAUGGAAGGGGUUAUAUAAACCUGGGCUAUGCUGGACAUCUACAGAAGAGUAUUACAUUCACUUGCAAAGUUUACAUUUUUGAGCUCACAGUUAUGAAAAAUAUGACCCACAAGUUUUUCAGGCAGGUGAGGAUGGGUCUUCUUGCAAAUGCAUGAGUUCUGUCUUGAGUCCUGGGAACUUCUCUGUUGGUUGAGUGUGGGCUCAUUCCCUGACUCUCCUAAUCAUGUUUGCGUCAGAAUGUUAGCAUUGUAAAUAAAAGAAUAGGUUGUAUAAUAGAUACACAACACUUGAAACUUUACUUUAAAAAAAUCGAUAGUUCUACAUAUAUAUUUAGUUAUAUCACUUGACAGAUUUCUUCUACACAGUGUGGAGAUUGUUUUAUACCACAGAUUAUUUUUAUAAAGUUAGUGAAUUUGAAUGAUUUUGUAAUCAGAGCUAAUGAGCUUUACCUUUCAAGAGAAACGUACACUGGAGCAUGAGUGGUGUGGAACUUUUACUUAGUGUUUAUAUGGAUUCUUGUGAUACACUGGCAGACUGGAGUCAAUUUGCGGGUCUUUUUUGGCCAAAACUCCACUUGUGGUUGUGUAGGACAGUGAUAUUCAGCUCAGCUUCUUGUGGAUUGGGAGGAGAGAGGGCCUGCAAUGUGUUUUACAUUGGUGCUUCCUCCUGAGAUUUCUGUUGAACAAAGGGUUCUGAGGUCAAAAAUUAGUUUGUAAGCCUUUGCCAUAGGACAUAGUCAUGUGAGAGUGUUUGGGGGAACAGAAAUUGUAUAGGGGUGCCUAUUGGGGUGGGAUGGGACUCGAAUAAGAUUCAGGUACAAAAACUUUGAAAUGAGAAUCUGGUGGUUUGAGUAAUCCACCAGACUGAAUUAUCUAAGAUCACAUUAUCCAGGUUGGGGGGCAGAAUUACCCAGUUAAGUAAUUGUUCAGAAAAGUGGGGAGGGUGGCAUGUGGAUGCAGUGAUCCAAUUAAAUGGAGAGCUGCCAGGCACAUUUUGUCCUCUCUGGUCAGUGAGAAUGGUUGGGUUGGCUCGCUGCUUCAAUCUGUGGAAUCAGCCAGGAGCCCAGUGAGGAAGCUCAGAACCCCAGUAACAGCAGAGCAUCUUUCAGAUAGCUCCAGAGUUUUCCUGCUUUUCUGAGGAAGCUCAGCAUCACUGCCACAAUACGGAAAGUGGUCUUCAUUUUAGCCUAUUUAUUUUUAGGCAGAGAGUGGAUGGUUAUUUGUGUGGGACUUUUGGUGGCGAUAUAUAAUGAAUAAUUAAGUUAAUUUCUGGUAUGCAUAAUGGCCAGUCCUGAGGCCCAGCUGAAGACCUGUCCCCCAGACCCUGCCCGCUGGCUUCAGGCUGCUGCUUCUAGACAGAGGUGCACUGGACGGGAUAGUUUUAUCAAGAGAAUCCCUAAUGUGUCAUUUUAAACCAGCUGUGCUUUUUAUUCAUUCUGGUUGAGCGUAUAGGUUUACACUUUACCCUUUUUAUACUUGGAAUAAAUUUAGUUCCAGCAGAUCUAGUAGCACUCCAGAAACCAACCCCAUCUGUUCCCCAUAAAAAGAACAUUUUCUCUGCUCUCCAGCCACGUGUCUUGGAAUGUAAUUCUGUUGUGCCUUUGUUUUUAUCACUCUCUUCGCCCCAAAAGCAACUGCUGUAAGCUUUUUUCUACUUGUCUUUUCUAGUCCCCAACCUCUACCUUUUUCCUUUUUCCCAGCCCUAAUUUCUGGAUGCACUUCUGUGAUCCAGGUAUUUUAAGAACCAGUUACCUCAGACCUCAUGUUGAACAGUGUCGCCAUCUGGGUCCUCUUGAUACUGCAGACUUUUAACGUACACAUGCAGGAACCCUGCUGAGCGUGGGCACUUGUUUUAAAGCAAAACUCUUCCCAAGGACUGAAGAAAGGGCUUCUGGCAAGCUCGUCAUGGCAUUGUGGUGGGAUGGGUCUAGAGUGUCAUCUGAAUGGUGCUUCCUGUGUUCCUCUUUGAAUUCUGCCAUUUUCAGUAUUCUUGUGUGUCUGAAUAGGCAAAGCGAUUUAAUUGGCUGGUCUUGCACGCAAAUUAGUUCCAAAGAUAAGCUCUUUGUAACACAUUUCCAGUCGCUAAUGCUCAAAUGUAGAACAUUCCUUUAAAUGGCAGGAUAAAAAACCCACUAUCCACCAUAGUGCAUUUUGGGAAGAUGUCUGUAGCAUAUGUUGCUGUGAAAUUAGGCCUUGUGGGAUAUGGCUGUUUGUCAUUUUGAUGUAUUUUAAAUAAAUAUAUAUAUUUUUUAAAGAGCCUUUUUUACCAGUUCAAAAAGUUUAAUUAACCAGCAGUCACCGCAUCUGAAUUUUUGUCUCUGGGGCAUAGAUGGCAGACCAAGAUUAAAAGUGGUAACUCAGCUAUACGAGCAUGGGCUACCUUCCUGGGCUCUCCUGCAGUCCUGUAGACCUGCUGUUCCGCAGACCAUGGGACACAAGGUCAGUGUGUUCCCAGUGAGGGUCCCAAGUCAGUCAUCUUAAGUGUUUGUUCUCUGCCCCAUUCAGUGGACUGUUGACUUCAGUCCCUGCAAGUGCUUUAGCCCGAGUGGGGUUUUCUCAGAGCACUGCCACGAGUUAAGUGUGUGUUUAGCCAAAUAAUUUCUCCGUAAGGGAAAAAUGCAGUCACCCAAAUUUUACCAACAAUGACAGAGAUGAGAGUAGAAAAGAUUAGGCAACAUCUGAGUUUUAACUUGAAAAGUGUCCAAGUCAUCAUGAAAGGCCGACUGGGAGCAAGUGAUUAUUAGAGAUUCUUCAGGAGACCUCAUCUGAAAAUGUUAAGACUGCCAGUGAGGGAAGGAAUUGUUAAAAUGCCAGCGGCUUUUUUUUCCUCUUUUUUUCUGUAAUUCUGUAAAAAUGCAGAGAAAGUUGAGUGGUACUUCAGAAUUGAGGGAGAGGGUUACCGCAGAGUAGAAAUAUAUUUCUAGAUUUCAGUUCCACACCACAAAUCCACAACAAUGCCAUUUUUCAACUGUACAAAAAUCUGCUUAUGAACUGGACAUGAUCUUAAUGGUAGUGUCAAAGGCCAAGUUUUUCACCUGUUAAUAUUUUUCCACAUUUGUCCUUGAAUCUGAAUAACUUUAUACAGUACUGUAAAUUUAACUUACAUCGAGUUUGUUGUCAAUUCUUAUGAAAAGAGCUUUCUGCAUGUAACACAUACGGUUAAAGAACACAGCAAAGGACAAAAUUUGCAGGAACAGUUUUGGAACCAACAGAAAAUGUCACCUUUUAUUUGCCAUCUUAUAUAUAUCUAUCAGUUUUACCAGCUACUUCUAAAUUUGUACAUUAUUUGUAAGGGAAAGAAGGAAAACCCUAAGACUUGUCUAACUUAGUGGAGAAUGUGUGUGUUGGGCUUAGGAUGGAUAGCUAAGUCUUAUUGAGCUGUGUUACCUAACUUGUAUAUAAAAAUUGUAAUUAAAAGUUUGGGUUCACCUGUUUCUCACAGUUUAAAAUGAUGAGUAAUUGCAAACUCUGGAAAUGUGACUAGUAUAUGAUUUAAGGCUGUAGAAGCAAGGAAGCUCUUUCAAGUGCUAAAACUAAAGACUUCUAGUUUUUGGCUCAAAUAAGUACUGUUUGUAUACCAGGAUAUGUGAGAUGUAAAUGUAGUAGGUCACUUUUCACCCUUGUAGCUAUAAAAUAAAAAUUUUGUAGAACAGAAAUAGCUUGUACUACUGAAUUAACAAAAGUUAUACUAAAGUAUCAUGUUUAAAAAAAAUAUAUAUAUAUAUACAGAGUUAAGCUUGUUGCUGUUACCCUGUCUGGAUUUGAAAAGUGUGCUGAUUUAUAUAUAUAUAUUACACACACACACACACACACACACACACACACACACACACACACACACACACACACACACACACACACACACAUACACCUAAAAUGGCCUAAAGCAGACAUCCAUGUAAUUACAGUUGCAAAAUGAAAACAUUUUGGAAAGAACAUUGUAUCAUAGUUCAUUCAUUUGCAGUGGAUCUUUGUUCCUUUUUACUGUGGUAAUUUUAGAAAUGAGUGUCAAGUUUGAAAUUAGAUCUGCUAAGUUGGGGUUUUGCUGCUUGAACUCUGCACUGGGUCCUCAAAUAAACCGAUGUGAAUGUAGUUUUUUCCCCCUGUGUGAAGAAGCAGUUACACCCCAACAAUAGGAGGAAAAAUCUAGAACUAUUUCAAGUUUUAUCUUUUUGUAUAUGAAAAUAAAAUAAUAAUAAAACAA